CUAUAUAAUGUUCUGCAGUGCUAGCUGCCAGCUCCUCCUCACAGAUGCACCUCCGGUGCUGUGGGUCGUAAUCUAGAAUACCAUCACUAGGUGACUAAGUCAUACUCACAUUCCUUUCAUUGACCUGGUGGCCAUAAAUUGUUUCCUCCCAUGCCUAAAGAUUCACAGAGAACAGAAAAGUACUAGAUUACUACAUUAUUAGCAGACUAAUGGUGGGAAAUGUCUAUAGUCAUCGACCUCUAUGUUUAUUUUAUUUUAUUUUAUUUUUUUAUUUUGAGAUGGAGUUUCACUCUUGUUCCCCAGGCUGGAGUGCAGUGGCGUGAUCUCGGCUCACUGCAACCUCUGCCUCCCUGAUUCAAGCGAUUCUCCUGCCUCAGCCUCCCAAGUAACUGGGAUUACAAGUGUGCACCACCACACGUGGCUAAUUUUUUGUAUUUUUAGUAGAGACAGGAUUUCACCAUGUUCGCCAGGCUGGUCUUGAACUCCUGACCUCAGGCGAUCCACCCGCCUCAGCUUCCCAAAGUGCUGGGAUUACAGGCGUGAGCCACUGCACCCAGGUUCUAUGUUGAUUUUAGAUGUAAUAGAUGAGUUAAUUGUAAUAUUCACCCCAGUGUCCUUUGCAAGGAAAAAAAUGCAAUUAUCCUUAUUCCUUAUGACAAUAAAAUGCAUGUUCUUUUAUGUUGAGGCUCUGUUUUGAGAAGUAAAAUAAAUUAUGUCUUUAGUACAAUAUAUGAAUUGUAUAUGGAAAAACAUGCUUUUUGAAAGUCCCACCAAAAAGGUUUCUUUAUGGUAUCAUUAAAUAUAAUUUCAGUUUUUAUAUGUAUACAUCAUCCCUGUCUCUCUUUCCAGGCCGGGCAUUUAUAUAUGUAUGGUCAGUAUAUUUUCUAUUAUUGGCACUUGGCAUCUCCUUUCCCCUGCUCCAGAAUGGUCUUUUCUGAUAAAACUCACAAGCUUUGCAUUACCACAAGCUCUGCUGCUAGAAGAGUGAAUCACAAGAAUGUUGUAUGCUUGGGGUGUUCUGUGUGCCUGUGUUGAUGUGUCUGUAUUCUAAUGAGCAAUCCAGUUUUACACUAGCAUACAGAUAUUUAACUCUGAGGUAUGUGUCCACAAAGCUGCUUUUGUCAUUUCACUAGUCAGUGGGUUUUGCUUGUGAGAGUUAGGGGGUUGAUUUGACCCGAGGCUUCUUAGAAGAAUUUUUUAACAUUCCAAGUUUAUCUAAUAGAUGUGCUAUGAAGAGAACAGAAUGAUGGGACUUUAAAAAAAUUUUUACAGUUAUUUUUAUUUUGUAGAAUGAGCUGAAAGCCAGUGGUGGCGAAAUCAAAAUUCAUAAAAUGGAGCAAAAGGAGAAUGUGCCCCCAGGUCCUGAGGUCUGCAUCACCCAUCAGGAAGGGGAAAAGAUUUCUGCAAAUGAGAAUAGCCUGGCAGUCCGUUCCACCCCUGCCGAAGAUGACUCCCGUGACUCCCAGGUUAAGAGUGAGGUUCAACAGCCUGUCCAUCCCAAGCCACUAAGUCCAGAUUCCAGAGCCUCCAGUCUUUCUGAAAGUUCUCCUCCCAAAGCAAUGAAGAAGUUUCAGGCACCUGCAAGAGAGACCUGCGUGGAAUGUCAGAAGACAGUCUAUCCAAUGGAGCGUCUCUUGGCCAACCAGCAGGUGUUUCACAUCAGCUGCUUCCGUUGCUCCUAUUGCAACAACAAACUCAGUCUAGGAACAUAUGCAUCUUUACAUGGAAGAAUCUAUUGUAAGCCUCACUUCAAUCAACUCUUUAAAUCUAAGGGCAACUAUGAUGAAGGCUUUGGGCACAGACCACACAAGGAUCUAUGGGCAAGCAAAAAUGAAAACGAAGAGAUUUUGGAGAGACCAGCCCAGCUUGCAAAUGCAAGGGAGACCCCUCACAGCCCAGGGGUAGAAGAUGCCCCUAUUGCUAAGGUGGGUGUCCUGGCUGCAAGUAUGGAAGCCAAGGCCUCCUCUCAGCAGGAGAAGGAAGACAAGCCAGCUGAAACCAAGAAGCUGAGGAUCGCCUGGCCACCCCCCACUGAACUUGGAAGUUCAGGAAGUGCCUUGGAGGAAGGGAUCAAAAUGUCAAAGCCCAAAUGGCCUCCUGAAGACGAAAUCAGCAAGCCCGAAGUUCCUGAGGAUGUCGAUCUAGAUCUGAAGAAGCUAAGACGAUCUUCUUCACUGAAGGAAAGAAGCCGCCCAUUCACUGUAGCAGCUUCAUUUCAAAGCACCUCUGUCAAGAGCCCAAAAACUGUGUCCCCACCUAUCAGGAAAGGCUGGAGCAUGUCAGAGCAGAGUGAAGAGUCUGUGGGUGGAAGAGUUGCAGAAAGGAAACAAGUGGAAAAUGCCAAGGCUUCUAAGAAGAAUGGGAAUGUGGGAAAAACAACCUGGCAAAACAAAGAAUCUAAAGGAGAGACAGGGAAGAGAAGUAAGGAAGGUCAUAGUUUGGAGAUGGAGAAUGAGAAUCUUGUAGAAAAUGGUGCAGACUCCGAUGAAGAUGAUAACAGCUUCCUCAAACAACAAUCUCCACAAGAACCCAAGUCUCUGAAUUGGUCGAGUUUUGUAGACAACACCUUUGCUGAAGAAUUCACUACUCAGAAUCAGAAAUCCCAGGAUGUGGAACUCUGGGAGGGAGAAGUGGUCAAAGAGCUCUCUGUGGAAGAACAGAUAAAGAGAAAUCGGUAUUAUGAUGAGGAUGAGGAUGAAGAGUGACAAAUUGCAAUGAUGCUGGGCCUUAAAUUCAUGUUAGUGUUAGCGAGCCACUGCCCUUUGUCAAAAUGUGAUGCACAUAAGCAGGUAUCCCAGCAUGAAAUGUAAUUUACUUGGAAGUAACUUUGGAAAAGAAUUCCUUCUUAAAAUCAAAAACAAAACAAAAAAACACAAAAAACACAUUCUAAAUACUAGAGAUAACUUUACUUAAAUUCUUCAUUUUAGCAGUGAUGAUAUGCAUAAGUGCUGUAAGGCUUGUAACUGGGGAAAUAUUCCACCUGAUAAUAGCCCAGAUUCUACUGUAUUCCCAAAAGGCAAUAUUAAGGUAGACAGAUGAUUAGUAGUAUAUUGUUACACACUAUUUUGGAAUUAGAGAACAUACAGAAGGAAUUUAGGGGCUUAAACAUUACGACUGAAUGCACUUUAGUAUAAAGGGCACAGUUUGUAUAUUUUUAAAUGAAUACCAAUUUAAUUUUUUAGUAUUUACCUGUUAAGAGAUUAUUUAGUCUUUAAAUUUUUUAGGUUAAUUUUCUUGCUGUGAUAUAUAUGAGGAAUUUACUACUUUAUGUCCUGCUCUCUAAACUACAUCCUGAACUCGACGUCCUGAGGUAUAAUACAACAGAGCACUUUUUGAGGCAAUUGAAAAACCAACCUACACUCUUCGGUGCUUAGAGAGAUCUGCUGUCUCCCAAAUAAGCUUUUGUAUCUGCCAGUGAAUUUACUGUACUCCAAAUGAUUGCUUUCUUUUCUGGUGAUAUCUGUGCUUCUCAUAAUUACUGAAAGCUGCAAUAUUUUAGUAAUACCUUCGGGAUCACUGUCCCCCAUCUUCCGUGUUAGAGCAAAGUGAAGAGUUUAAAGGAGGAAGAAGAAAGAACUGUCUUACACCACUUGAGCUCAGACCUCUAAACCCUGUAUUUCCCUUAUGAUGUCCCCUUUUUGAGACACUAAUUUUUAAAUACUUACUAGCUCUGAAAUAUAUUGAUUUUUAUCACAGUAUUCUCAGGGUGAAAUUAAACCAACUAUAGGCCUUUUUCUUGGGAUGAUUUUCUAGUCUUAAGGUUUGGGGACAUUAUAAACUUGAGUACAUUUGUUGUACACAGUUGAUAUUCCAAAUUGUAUGGAUGGGAGGGAGAGGUGUCUUAAGCUGUAGGCUUUUCUUUGUACUGCAUUUAUAGAGAUUUAGCUUUAAUAUUUUUUAGAGAUGUAAAACAUUCUGCUUUCUUAGUCUUACCUAGUCUGAAACAUUUUUAUUCAAUAAAGAUUUUAAUUAAAAUUUGAA